GACGCGGCUGCCGGAAGCGGGUCUGGAGCGGGCGAGACGGCCAGGGCCGGCGAGCGCAGUGCAGCGCCGCGCGGUGCGGGCGGCCGAGUGGGGGCGUCAUGGAGGAUGAGCGGAGCUUUUCGGAUAUCUGCGGCGGCCGCCUGGCGCUGCAGCGCCGCUACUACUCCCCGUCCUGCCGGGAAUUCUGCCUCAGCUGCCCUCGGCUCUCGCUGCGUUCGCUCACCGCUGUCACCUGCACGGUGUGGCUGGCGGCCUACGGACUCUUCACCCUCUGCGAGAACAGCAUGAUCCUCUCUGCUGCCAUCUUCAUCACCCUCUUAGGUCUGCUUGGUUAUCUCCAUUUUGUGAAGAUUGAUCAGGAGACUCUGUUAAUCAUUGAUUCCCUUGGCAUUCAGAUGACUUCAUCUUAUGCUUCAGGCAAAGAAAGCACUACCUUCAUAGAAAUGGGCAAGGUCAAGGAUAUUGUCAUCAAUGAGGCCAUUUACAUGCAGAAGGUGAUUUACUACCUCUGCAUCUUAUUGAAAGAUCCAGUGGAACCACAUGGGAUAUCCCAAGUAGUACCCGUCUUCCAGAGACAGAGUCUCACUUUGUCACCUAGGCUGGAGUGCAGUGACAAUCACCACUCAUUGCAGCCUCCACCUCCCAGGCUCAAGAAAUCCUCCUGCCUCAGCCUCCUGAGAACUUGGGACUACAGAGUGCCAAGCCCCGGCUGGACUGCUUGAUUGAAGUAUACAGGAGCUGCCAGGAGAUCCUGGCACACCAGAAAGCCACAUCAACAAGCCCAUGAGCCCCAGCGUUCAGAAGGCCAGCAUUGUCUUCCAUGGGAGAUGACUCUUAAGCCAUAGGGGCUGGUUUUCCGUACUCCAAACCAUCAGGUGGACACAGUCCUAGGAACCAUUAUGGAUGUAGUGCAUCUUAGAGCCAUAGAGCAGGUGACUGGAAAUCUAACUCAGUAUAUUUCCGUGUAUUAUAGUGUUUUCCUUGUAAGGUUUUGCCUACUUUACCAAAGGAGGGGAGACCUUAAGAAUUUUGACACAGUAUGUCAAAAGUAAUGUCAGCAAAGAACACUUUCGGAAAUUGCUAAGCAUGUUCAGGUUUACUUUGUUGAUGUUUGUGAAGCAAAACAAUGGGAAACUGACAUCAGAUGUCUUGAGAAAGCUAUAUUUUCCAAUAGUACCCCUUGUGUAAAGUUACGAAAAAAACAAGCCCUUCAGUACUGGUUAGCAGGAAGAAAUGUCCUACAAAAGACGAGUCUGUCAACCUAGUGCCUGUGUUCUGUACAGGGCUUAUUUAUUUACUGUUAAUAAACAGAUCUUCCAAAACACACAGUUACCUGGUUCACAGAUAGCUGCUUUUUAUUGACAAACAAGAUCAUAGUAUUUCAGUCAUGGUGUCAAGCACAUUAAUACUUUUCUGUUACUCAGCAUUUUUUUUUAUAUCAGUUCAAAAGCUACUUUUGCCAAGAAGGAUGAGACAAAAGGCCAGACAGAAAUUGGACUUUGGUUUUCAGACAUGGGACUCUCAUGUUAACAAAGAAUAAAUAAGCAAAUAUUGAAUCCUU